GCAGAGACAAGGCUGGAUUUGGCUUUUCUAAGCAACAUGUGUUCCUGCGCAGGGCUGAAUGGUCACUGAGACAGAGAUGGAAGCCAGGACAAGGGAGCCCACCGGGCCCAGAUAGAGACUUCAGAACCCACUCCUGAGAACAGCGGAGCCAGGCGCUUAGAGGAAGACCAAAUGCUGCCAGGACACGGAUUGUCCAGGAUUACAUUCCAGCAUCUUAUUAGAUGGGGUUUGCUACAUUGCCCAGACUGGUCUCAAACACCUGGGUUCAGUUGUCCUGCCUCGGCCUCCCAAAGUGCUGGGAUUACAGGCAUGAGCCACCACACUCGAACACUUGGGGUGGUUUUAAGCCCCCAGCAAGGUGCACCAGCAGGACCAGGAGGUGGCCUGGGCACCCCCUAUCACUCCCAUCCAUGCAAACCUAGGCAAGUCCCUGUCUCUGAAUCUCAGCCACCACCACAUACAAUGCAAGUCGGAAGAUGGGCAGGACUGGGGGUGGGGCAGGCAGAGGCCACCUCUGUCAGGCUGGGGUUGCAUGGGCUGGAGCCUGUCUUCCCAUACCUGGGACAUGACCUCCAAGGACCAGCUGUCAGUCAUGGUGAUGGGCUGGCUGGGGUUGGCAGGGAGCUUGCUCUCCUUCUCGGAGGGCCGGAGCAGCGUGGGGCCAAACACCGUGCCAAGGUUGUGCAGGGACAUCUUAUUGACUGCCUCCUUCUCUGCCAUCCUGUAGAGGACCGAAGCAGAGGGUGCUGUUUCAACGCCACCACCAGGAGAGAGGCAGAGGGGCUGUGCCGUGCUAGAGUCCUCAGGGAGGGAGUGACCUCGACCCUGGCUGUGCUGCAAGCUGACUCCAGCCUUGGUGUCAGCAGCACCCGGCGAACAGCAGCAGGAGGAGCCGCUAGAGCAGCUGCUCAUGGGCAGAGCUGCCCUCGGGCAACUCCUGCCACCACCCCCUCCCCAGGGAGCCCAAGGCAGGGGAGGCUCAGCAUGGAAUGAAACAGGGGAGUGAGGGACACAAGGAGGUGGGAAGUGGGAGGGUCCCAGCCCCACCAAGUACACAGAGACCCCCUCGACAUCCUGGACACCACAGGGGCACCUGCAGGCUGGGAGACCAGGUCCUCUGUGCAUGGGCCCGGGAGGCAGACCUGCCCUAAGGGUGAUGCACAGGCUACAGGUGCUGCACGCUCCAGCGCCCACUCUAGACAUCAGCCUCCAGGUUGACUAAGGGUCAGGUCAUGUUUGAAACCAUGCUUGGCUGGACCAGGACCCAUGGCAAGAGCACCUGGGCACCAGUGUUUAGCCCUGGUCUGCAGGAAGGAGGACAGCAGACUUUAGGACCCCACAGCACGGCAGUGCUGACCAUUUCACCCACUUGGCCUCCUUGAGAAAUAUGGAUGGGGACCCCUCUGGGGAUGGGCAAGGCCUUCCAGGAUAGGCUCAGUUUUGGUCCCCUGCUUUUUGAGGUUGGGUUAAAAUUCCGACCAUGGCAGAGGAAGCACAGCUCAGGUUCCCACACCUCACUUUUCACAGCCUCUGAGGGCAGCAGUGCACGUGGAGGAGACGUCUCCCAUGAGGCCAAGGCCUCCAGUGCUCACCGAUGCCCUCUGCGAAGUUGGGGUAGAACUCGUCAGUGAAGAGGGGCUCGGGCAGCUCACGGAAAUACAGCUUCAGCGUGCCUGCGAUGGCGUUCACGUCCAUCUCGCUCAUCAUCACUGACACGUCCUUGUUAUCUGGAAAGAGCACGGAAAUGCAGCGGCCUCCUUGAAGAUCCUGAUAAAUGAAGAAAAGACACAGAGAAGGAUGUGACAUGCCUGGGCCAUGGAGCACUCUGAGAUCUCAUCGUGGACACCACUGCCCACACCUC